AACUAAAGCCGGGAGUCCGGUGAACGGGCAGAAGCAGGGCCAUGCCCAAGCCACCCCCAAGAUCCCCCUGAACCUGCACCUCCAUCACGACCCAUUCAGGAGCCUCCAGGAGCCCAGACACCAGCCCCCCACCAUGGGCAGCAAGGAGCGCUUCCACUGGCAGAGCCACAACGUGAAGCAGAGCGGCGUGGAUGACAUGGUGCUUCUUCCCCAGAUCACCGAAGACGCCAUUGCCGCCAACCUCCGGAAGCGCUUCAUGGACGACUACAUCUUCACCUACAUCGGCUCUGUGCUCAUCUCUGUAAACCCCUUCAAGCAGAUGCCCUACUUCACCGACCGUGAGAUCGACCUCUAUCAGGGCGCGGCCCAGUAUGAGAAUCCCCCGCACAUCUACGCCCUCACGGACAACAUGUACCGGAACAUGCUUAUCGACUGUGAGAACCAGUGUGUCAUCAUUAGUGGAGAGAGUGGAGCUGGGAAGACAGUGGCAGCCAAAUAUAUCAUGGGCUACAUCUCCAAGGUGUCUGGCGGAGGCGAGAAGGUCCAGCACGUCAAAGAUAUCAUCCUGCAGUCCAACCCGCUGCUCGAGGCCUUCGGCAACGCCAAGACUGUGCGCAACAACAAUUCCAGCCGCUUUGGCAAGUACUUUGAGAUCCAGUUCAGCCGAGGUGGGGAGCCAGAUGGGGGCAAGAUCUCCAACUUCUUGCUGGAGAAGUCCCGCGUGGUCAUGCAAAAUGAAAAUGAGAGGAACUUCCACAUCUACUACCAGCUGCUGGAAGGGGCCUCCCAGGAGCAAAGGCAGAACCUGGGCCUCAUGACACCGGACUACUAUUACUACCUCAACCAAUCGGACACCUACCAGGUGGACGGCACGGACGACAGAAGCGACUUUGGUGAGACUCUGAGUGCUAUGCAGGUUAUUGGGAUCCCGCCCAGCAUCCAGCAGCUGGUCCUGCAGCUCGUGGCGGGGAUCUUGCACCUGGGGAACAUCAGUUUCUGUGAAGACGGGAAUUACGCCCGAGUGGAGAGUGUGGACCUCCUGGCCUUUCCCGCCUACCUGCUGGGCAUUGACAGCGGGCGACUGCAGGAGAAGCUGACCAGCCGCAAGAUGGACAGCCGCUGGGGCGGGCGCAGCGAGUCCAUCAAUGUGACCCUCAACGUGGAGCAGGCAGCCUACACCCGUGAUGCCCUGGCCAAGGGGCUCUAUGCCCGCCUCUUCGACUUCCUCGUGGAGGCCAUCAACCGUGCUAUGCAGAAACCCCAGGAAGAGUACAGCAUCGGUGUGCUGGACAUUUACGGCUUCGAGAUCUUCCAGAAAAAUGGCUUCGAGCAGUUUUGCAUCAACUUCGUCAAUGAGAAGCUGCAGCAAAUCUUUAUCGAACUUACCCUGAAGGCCGAGCAGGAGGAGUAUGUGCAGGAAGGCAUCCGCUGGACUCCAAUCCAGUACUUCAACAACAAGGUCGUCUGUGACCUCAUCGAAAACAAGCUGAGCCCCCCAGGCAUCAUGAGCGUCUUGGACGACGUGUGCGCCACCAUGCACGCCACGGGCGGGGGAGCAGACCAGACACUGCUGCAGAAGCUGCAGGCGGCUGUGGGGACCCACGAGCAUUUCAACAGCUGGAGCGCCGGCUUCGUCAUCCACCACUACGCUGGCAAGGUCUCCUACGACGUCAGCGGCUUCUGCGAGAGGAACCGAGACGUUCUCUUCUCCGACCUCAUAGAGCUGAUGCAGACCAGUGAGCAGGCCUUCCUCCGGAUGCUCUUCCCCGAGAAGCUGGAUGGAGACAAGAAGGGGCGCCCCAGCACCGCCGGCUCCAAGAUCAAGAAACAAGCCAACGACCUGGUGGCCACACUGAUGAGGUGCACACCCCACUACAUCCGCUGCAUCAAACCCAACGAGACCAAGAGGCCCCGAGACUGGGAGGAGAACAGGACUGGUGACUCCCCACCCCGAGGGGACUCAGCCUACCCUCCCCACCAGAGUCAAGCACCAGGUGGAAUACCUGGGCCUGAAGGAGAACAUCAGGGUGCGCAGAGCCGGCUUCGCCUACCGCCGCCAGUUCGCCAAAUUCCUGCAGAGCCCUCCGCCCUCAGGUAUGCCAUUCUGACCCCCGAGACGUGGCCGCGGUGGCGUGGGGACGAACGCCAGGGCGUCCAGCACCUGCUUCGGGCGGUCAACAUGGAGCCCGACCAGUACCAGAUGGGGAGCACCAAGGUCUUUGUCAAGAACCCAGAGUCGCUUUUCCUCCUGGAGGAGGUGCGAGAGCGAAAGUUCGAUGGCUUUGCCCGAACCAUCCAGAAGGCCUGGCGGCGCCACGUGGCUGUCCGGAAGUACGAGGAGAUGCGGGAGGAAGCUUCCAACAUCCUGCUGAACAAGAAGGAGCGGAGGCGCAACAGCAUCAAUCGGAACUUCGUCGGGGACUACCUGGGGCUGGAGGAGCGGCCCGAGCUGCGUCAGUUCCUGGGCAAGAGGGAGCGGGUGGACUUCGCCGAUUCGGUCACCAAGUACGACCGCCGCUUCAAGCCCAUCAAGCGGGACUUGAUCCUGACGCCCAAGUGUGUGUAUGUGAUUGGGCGAGAGAAAGUGAAGAAGGGACCUGAGAAGGGCCAGGUGUGUGAAGUCUUGAAGAAGAAAGUGGACAUCCAGGCUCUGCGGGGAGUCUCCCUCAGCACGCGACAGGACGACUUCUUCAUCCUCCAAGAGGAUGCCGCCGACAGCUUCCUGGAGAGCGUCUUCAAGACCGAGUUUGUCAGCCUUCUGUGCAAGCGCUUCGAGGAGGCGACGCGGAGGCCCCUGCCCCUCACCUUCAGCGACACACUACAGUUUCGGGUGAAGAAGGAGGGCUGGGGCGGUGGCGGCACCCGCAGCGUCACCUUCUCCCGCGGCUUCGGCGACUUGGCAGUGCUCAAGGUUGGCGGUCGGACCCUCACGGUCAGCGUGGGCGAUGGGCUGCCCAAGAGCUCCAAGCCUACGCGGAAGGGAAUGGCCAAGGGAAAACCUCGGAGGUCGUCCCAAGCCCCUACCCGGGCGGCCCCUGCGCCCCCCAGAGGCAUGGAUCGCAAUGGGGUGCCCCCCUCUGCCAGAGGGGGCCCCCUGCCCCUGGAGAUCAUGUCUGGAGGGGGCACCCACAGGCCUCCCCGGGGCCCUCCGUCCACAUCCCUGGGAGCCAGCAGACGACCCCGGGCACGUCCGCCCUCAGAGCACAACACAGAAUUCCUCAACGUGCCUGACCAGGGCAUGGCCGGCAUGCAGAGGAAGCGCAGCGUGGGGCAACGGCCAGUGCCUGGUGUGGGCCGACCCAAGCCCCAGCCUCGGACACAUGGUCCCAGGUGCCGGGCCCUAUACCAGUACGUGGGCCAAGAUGUGGACGAGCUGAGCUUCAACGUGAACGAGGUCAUUGAGAUCCUCAUGGAAGAUCCCUCGGGCUGGUGGAAGGGCCGGCUUCACGGCCAGGAGGGCCUUUUCCCAGGAAACUACGUGGAGAAGAUCUGAGCUGGGCCCUGGGAUACUGCCUUCUCUUUCGCCCGCCUAUCUGCCUGCCGGCCUGGUGGGGAGCCAGGCCCUGCCAAUGAGAGCCUCGUUUACCUGGGCUGCAAUAGCCUAAAAGUCCAGUCCUUUGGCCUCCAGUCCUGCCCAGGCCCUGGGUCACCAGGUCACUGCUGCAGCCCCCGCCCCUGGGCCCUGGUCUUCCUCCAACAUCACACCUGCUGCCCAUUCUCCAUUUCUGUGUGUGUCAAAGGGGACUAACAGCAGAAUCUACCUCCCAACUGCCAUGUGAUUAAGAAAUGGGUCUUGAGUCCUGUGCUGUUGGCAAAGUGCCAGGCACAGUUGGGGAGGGGGGGGUCCUUAACAAGCGUGACUUUGCUCAUUCUGUCAUCACUAAGGCAAUAAACCUUUGCCAGGUGAAAGCACGAGUUAACUUACUAAGUGCCCAACAAGGACGAUGUUUUCACAGCCCUGUGAGGUAGGAGCUGUGAAGGACCCCAUCUUACAGGUGGAACAAUGGAGGUUCAGAGAGGUUCACUGACCCAAGACUGCACAGAGCCAUGCCUUGCAUUCAUAUGUGACCAUAAAGCUUGAAUUUGUCCCAGUUUGGGCUGGGCGCAGUGGCUCACGCCUGUAAUCCCAGCACUUUGGGAGGCUGAGGCGGGCAGAUCACGUGAGACCAGGAGUUCAAGACCAGCCUGGAUAACACAGCAAAACCCUGUUUCUACUAAAAAUUUAAAAAAGAAAAAAAAAAAA